ACUAUGUGGAAGCAUGAACAGAUCUUAAAGUGUGCUAGGUAAGGGGGAAUGAAUUAUGGGUAAGAUGGUUUAGAUGAAGAUACAAGUCCACGAAUUGCAGUUCACAUCAUCAUGAGUGCAUUUCCUUCAGGGCAUAACCCUGGAGUUGAAGAUAUGAAUCAAGUGACAUUUUCUGCAGGUUGUGUUUGUAGAAGCUCUCAGACUUUUGUCAGGUUCUCCAAAUAUCUGUCCCCUCCUGUUGUUGUCUCUAAAAUGUUAGUACAGUAUUGCGCAGUUCUCCUCUAGUUUUCCUUGCGGAGGGGCUGCGUGGAUUAAUUAACAGAUUACUAGCAAAUGCUUUGAAAAUCAAAAGGUCCUUCAGGAAUAAUCAGCAUUGUUCGGUUCUCCUUUUGAAUGAGUAGAAAGGAUAUCUGAUUUCUUCAAAGCAAUAUAACUAAGAUGGAAGAGAGUGUUUCUCUUGCAGUGAUGCUAACUACUGUGUUCUGAUGCACUACUCAGGUUGUAUUAUCAUGCCAUUAUUACAAGUGAAGAAAUAAAUGGGACCUCACUGGGUCUGCCAGAACCUCACUGCUGCAGAGCAUUACAAACACAUUAAAGUGUAAUUGACAUCUAGUAGCUGUAUGUCUAUAAUGUGCCAAUUAGAAUAUUUAGCUUUGCAAUAAAAGAGGAGUUAAUAAAACACAUUUAAGAAAUGGAAAAUAAGAUUAGAAGUGGCAUUUUGGCUCUUAUUCAAGUGGCAGGGAACAGAAGAGGGUGUGGAAACCAAGCUCAGCUCAGUUCCCUGUGUCUUCAUUCGUCACUGGCUCGUUCAUUACCAAAUGUCUAUAGAUAUUCAGAUACCACCCCUUCCUCCAAAGUAUUCUACUCUCCGUUUGAUUCAGUACUAUUUUAUAGCUUAAUGUCAUAUGGAAGUUUUAGAAUUCAGCUCCAAAGUAAACAGUAAAAUGAGUUAAAAUUACAGUUCAUUGAUUUCUUGCUGGCUUUUUAAUUUAUUUGUAAAACAAAUUGCAUAGAGUUUCUACUUUCUUCCCCUCAAAACUCACAACCCCAAAAAUAUCUGGCAGGGGGAGGGGGCUUUUAUUUUAACCACGAGUGAACUACUGUUUAGCAACAUUGACUACAAAUGUGCUUCUUGGGAAUUUCACCACUAUAUAAUUGCCUUCUUCAUUUCUUUUCUUGCUUAACUAGUGUAUAUAAUCACUGAUUUAUAAGUGUGAGCUGUAAUAAUGUCAGCUGUCUGCUGGCAUGAUUGGAGAACUUAUUAUGAAAUGAAGUUAAUUUUAUAUCUUCUUUUCUUGGAAACUCUUUUAUACUUAAUUUUAAGCAGAUAAGUGACAUAAAAGACCAAACUACUUGAAGAUAAUGCAUUUAGAAAUUGCUGAUUGAUGAGCUUAUGCUUAUCUAAUUUUGUUUUAAAAAGAUUCUAAUAUAUCUUUUGAGAAUAGAUUUUUGAGUGGAAGAACAAAACUAGUGUAGGUGGAUAAGAUACCAGCAAAAGAAAAAUGGAAGGGUUCUGUUUCCCUCUGUCCCAAAAUUAUUUUAAUGUUAAUCCUAGAAUUCAUGUUUUAGUCAUGGUUGUCAGUUGUGGAAAAUAUUAUUUAGUUUAAUAGUUUUACUUAAAAUAAAUGUUUGUGUUUUAAGCAAAACAGUUUAUGUUGUAAAAGGGUAACAGCUACAUUUUAUGCAUCUCUUUUUGCUGGAUUUUCUUUUAGAGAUAAUGAUCUUUAGGGCUGUUUUCUAUAAAUAUGCAUAUCGUACUUGUGUUUCUGUUUAAAUGCAUGCGUAAGAAGAACUGAAUUUGAUUAACUUUAUUAACAAUAAAUAAUGAAGUGUACUCUUUUAUGUUAACCCUUAUUUCAUUGUGUAUCAGCCUUCAGACAUUUGGCUAUCUAGACAGGCAGUCAUUUAUAUCCUUUUAAAAAAAUUUAUUGCUCUUUUGACUAAUUGCUUUUUAUAUGACUUUUUAUAAGCCUUUUGCAUUGAUACCAUUUGUUAAAACACAGCCAGAAGAAGGCAGAGCAGCCUCGUUUUUCAAAACUUUAGUGUCAUUUUUAUAGACAAAUAACACUUGUAAAUGAUGGAUAAUAGCUAGCAGGAUGCUGUGUGGUAUAAAAUGUGCGUGAAUUAUAUUUUCUGGGAGUUAGAAGGUUAACUUGUCUAUGAACUAAUUGAAAAGCUUUAUGGUAAAUGCAUAGUGCUGUGUGCACAUUAUCGGCAUGACUUAAACCAGCUGAAAAAGGGAUUUUCCUUCCCUUGGGUAUUAUUCAUUAUCUCCUCCCCUUUUCUGGCUAGCUGAUGUAUAUGGAGAGUAUCUAAUCAUAAUGAAUCUAUAGAAUUUAUAAAAAAGAGAACAGCGUAGAUGCUUUUCACAAUGAGUUGGCAGUUAAUACGUUGCAUAUUAGAAAUGGGAUGGAGGUGAGUGCAGGCAUUGAAAUUAUCGCUGCAUGACGAUGUAUUUUUGUAUUUGCAUAGGCCUUGUUUAUCAAGAUGAUUGUGGUUUUUGACCCUGGGAAAGCAAAUGGUGAGAGAUAGACUUGGUUUCUUCUGCAACUUGCAAUGCAUAGGUAACAGGAAUUUAUCACAAGCUUUUUGUUGAGGAAGGCUAACUCACAUGUCUCUCUUUCUUCCUACAUUGGACAGUUGUGUUAAGUUGAAAACACACCAUCUUAAUUUAGUAGCAAUUCAGAUAUUCAGUCAAGAAUAUUAAUAUGUUAAUGAGAACUUCAGAAAUUUCACUUAUGCGAAAGUAAGACUUUCCUUGCCCAUUGAAGACAUGGCUGUAGGCAUCCAUCCAGAUUAUGUGGGAGGAGGUAGGUUUAGUGUCAUAUUGAUACUCUCCCCACCCGCUCCAGCUACUCUUUCUCAUUGAGUGAAUGCUGGGGAGAAAAGGAGUAGAGGAGGGGUAGGUGAUAGUAAGAAAUAGAAGGGAUUUCUCACUGGGUCUGGUCAUAUGCUGGCUUUGUGUUUUCUGGGCCUUGUUGCAAUUUAACAUCUCUUUUCUUUAUCAUUGUUGUUUAUCAGUUUUAUGACAAUCACCUAGAUUGAAUUUCUUUUCUUUUCUUUUCUUUUCUUUUCUUUUCUUUUUUUUUUGAGACGGAGUUUUGUUCUUGUUGCCCAGGCUGGAGUGCAGUGGCACGAUCUCGGCUCACUGCAACCUCCGCCUCCCGGGUUCAAGUGAUUCUUCUGCCUCAGCCUCCCGAGUAGCUGGGAUUACAGGUGCAUGCCACCAUGCCCGGCUAAGUUUGUAUUUUUAGUAGAUAUGGGGUUUCUCCAUGUUGGUCAGGAUGGUCUUGAACUCCUGACCUCAGGUGAUCCACCCGCCUCAGCCUCCCAAAGUUCUGGGGUUUAAGGUGUGAGCCACCGCGCCCAGCCUGAAUUUCUUUUCAUUUACCCUGAUUAGUAUAUCUGUGGAUUUAUGUCUUUUAACACUCCUGGAAACAUCUCAGUUAUCAUCUCCUUAAAUAUUCCCUUUCCUCCUUCCUUUCUAUUCUUUUCUUCUAGGUCUCCGAUGAGACAUAUUUUGGACCUUCUCAUUGUAUUCUCCAUUUAGGUUAACAUUUCUUUAUAUUUUUCAUUUCCUUGUCUUACUGUAUUGCCUUUUAGGUAAUUUUUUCAUUUCUUCCUUCCAAUUCACUAAUUCUAUUUUUAGCUUUGACUAAAUGCUGUAUAAUCUUGCUAGCAAAUUUUUUUAUUUCAAUAAUCAUAGUUUUUAUUUUAAAAAGUUUUAGUUCUUUUAAAAUCUUCCUUGUCAUUUAAAAAAUUGUGGUAAAAUACACAUAGCAUAAAAUUCACCAUCUUCGCUAUUUUUAAGUGUACGCAGUUCAGUUAAUAUUAAGUACAUUCACGUUGUUAUGCAGCCAAUCUCCACAGCUCUUUUCAGUUUGCAAAGCUGAAACUGCCUGGUCAUUUUUUUUUUUUUUUUUUUUUGAGAUGGAGUUUCGCUCAUUGUUGCCCAGGCUGGAAUGCAGUGGCGCGAUCUUGGCUUACUGAAACCUCCGCCUCCCAGGUUCAAGUGAUUCUCCUGCCUCAGCCUCCCGAGUACCUGGGAUUACAGGCAAGUGCCACCACGCCUGGCUAAUUUUUGUAUUUUUAGUAGAGACGGGGUUUCACCAUGUUGGCCAGGCUGGUCCUGAACUCCUGGACUCAGGUGAUCCACCCGCCUUGGCCUCCCAAAGUGGUGGGAUUACGGUCGUGAGCCACUGCACCCAGCCCUGCCUGGUCAUUUUUGAUAGUCACUUGUUACUUAUUUAUUUUUGUGAUUAUGUCUUUUACUUCUUUAGCCUUUCAUAUGUAGUUAUUUUAUAGUCAGUAUUUGGUAACUGAAGCAUCUGAAGUCCUUGGCACUUUGCAUCUGUUCUUUCUCUCACUCCUGAUGUUUCGUUUCCCUGUCUGUUUAGUAAACCUUAAUUGCUAGCUCAUAUUUGGUUGAUCCUAAUUGUAGAAAAAGUCUUGGGGCCUAAGUCAAGGAUGCUUUUCUCAGAGUAUUUGCUUUUGCUUUUGCCAGUAGUCAUAGGGUGCUGCUGUCCUGCGGGGGUACUGCGGUCCUGAGACAAUUCCAUUGCCUUCCAGAUGCUGCCAUGUAACCCCGGAAUUUUAGUUUAGUUCCCCCACCCAGCCACAGAGCUGAGGCCCAGCCUCCCAGAGAUCACGUGAGAUCACCACAUGUCCUCACAGGACCGUUCCCCUUUUCUGAGGCUCACUGCCCAGGGAUUUUUGGUUGUUACUGUUUGUUCCUUUUCCUUUUUGCCCCUGUAGACAUUUUUUUUUCAUUUCCUCUGAACCCAACAAAACAAUAAUAAUUGGUUUUCAUUCAUUCAUUACUGGUAGACAGUAAAACAACAAGAGUAUUAGUCUGCCAUACUUCUGGAAGCCUGAGCUGGUUUUAAAGGGCCUUCCACAUGGGCACUCCGUGUGCUCCUCUGCUGGGCCCCUCCAACUGCAGCCACCUUACUCUGGCAGCCUUGCCUUCCCUUGCUCCCACAUUGCUCGCAGCUUCUGAUUUUAUGAGAUCUGCCUCAUCCAGACCCUGCUGGGUCCAUCUGACCCCCUGGAAGAAAUCUCUUGGGCAGGAUGACCUUGGUCGACAUCCCCAUCAUAAAUUCUACAUCUGGCUUCCCAAAUUAAGGUGCCUUUCCUCCACUUCAGAGGGAGAAUGCAGUUCAGGUCCUUCCCAGUGCAAUUUUAGCUAGCCUCUAUCUUUUAGCUGUGUACCAGCUGCCAGUCCAGCAGGCCUCCAAAAUUCUACGGAAAUUAUAUCAAGUGCUGUGCAUUUCUGCUUUGAAGCCUCUGUCAGUGGACUUGAGAGUCGGCACCCCCCCCCCCUCCACUGUGCUACCCAUCUCUUUGGUGAUGGUGGAGGGGAUCACAGCACAGCUCUUUUUUUCCCCCUCAAAGAAAAACAAAAUUCUCUGUUGACUUCUGUUUCUCACUCAGAGUAGGUCGGGGUAUAAAAAAUCAUGAAUCUAGUUAUGACACAUUAACUUUGAAAAGCUCCUUUGGAGAGCCUGGCACCUCACUUUGGAAAUUUAUAUCUGUCAUUGCUUGGAAACUUACUUGAAACUUCCAGUUUAAUACCUGCCCAUACAAACAUGCAGCAUGUGUUGCCUCCAUCAUGGGAUAGUUUUUUCUCCUUUCUCUGACUCCUGUUGUUUGUUAAACAUCAUCUAGAAUGGAAUGGACUUCCCUCUUUCCAUGCUGGCCAGUUGUUUUACUUUUUUGUCACCUUGGAGAUAGUGCUUCUUACCUCCUGUGAUUCUGAGACAUAAAGAUGAUCAGGAAGCCAUUACAGCCACUGCAGAGUCAGCAACAAUAGGGAAGGGCCGUACACUGUCACUUGGCAUGUUGUUUUAUUUUUUUUAAUGCCAUACGGAUUAACCAUCAUUAAAAAUAAGGUUAUAUUUAUAUAGUUACUCCCCAUUAAGGAGAUGGAGCUUAACUCCUCAUUCCUACAGCAUGGGCUGCACUUUGGGACUUAGCUUCAAACAUCACACUAGGGCAAGGAAAGAAAGUAACUUAGAGGUGGAGAAACCUGGCAAACAGUUUCUCAUCCCAGUGAUCAGUUCACAUCGACUAUGUCACACCUUGACAGGAUGUGGUGAGAAGGAUGUUUCAUCUCUGUGACCUGAAAAACCCAUAAUCUGGGUCUAGUGAUGAGUGAGAAAAGCAUCAGUCAAACCUACAUUGAGGGAUAUUUUACCAAAUGCCUGGCAGUGUUCCUCAAGACCAUCAACGUCAUCGAAAACAAGGGAAGUCUGAGCAAAGUGUCACUGACCAGGCCAGGCAAAGGAGCCAUGAGCUCUAAACGUAGUGGGAUGGGAUCUUGGGACAGAAAAGGACAUUAAGGGGAAAAAAGUUGUGAAAUCCAAAGAAAGUGUAGCGUGUAGUCAAUAGUAUCAUACCAGUGUUGCCUCCCUCAUUGUGACAGAUGUACGUAGUAAUGUCAAUGGUAACAACAGAAUAAACCAAGUGAGGGGUAUCCAGGGGGUGAGGGGUAUACAAGGGUUCUCUGCACUAUCUUUGUAAAGUUUUUGUACCCCUAAAUGUAAAACUAUUUAAAAUUCUAUUUAAGUAGAAUUUUUAAAUAUUUUUAAAUAAAAAUAAAUAUUUAAAUCAUUUAUCUAAUAGCUCAGAGAGCUGAUAUAUAUCUAUAGUGUUACCUGUAUUUCAGCAACACCUGUGACCAUCUUUCAGAAGGGAUGAGAAAUUGUGGUGGAAAAGGUAGCCCGGUUAAGCAGGCGGCGCUUAGCACAGUGGUUAAGGCAUAGCCUUUGGAGCCAAAAUGACUGGGUUUGAAGCCCUAUUUUGUUCCUUCUAGCUUUGUGACCUUAGGCAAGUUGACAUUCCUGUGCCUCAGUAUCUCUUCCUGUAAGAUGAUCACCCUGUGUUGAGUGACUAAUGAGGUAACACAUGUAAAGCUUAUCUGGCAUAGGCUACAUCUCUGUUGUAGCACCAGGACUUUCACUGUAUUUUUCCAACUUCUUCAAGUGACUAUAAAGGUGACAAGUUUGUGGAUAACACAGAGCUGAGCAAGCUCCUAUGAAAUUACCUGUUCUCGGAGGCUGGGGUUGAACCAAAGGAGGAUGGAGGGUGUGUUUCCCUCAUGGGUUGGGAGUGUCCCCUUCACGUGUGUGUGUGGGACCCCUUGGGUGUUCUCUAACUGCACACGAGUGGAUCAGAAGGAUACACUUAGUCAUAGGCAUUUUGUGUUUGUUGUUACACAGAACGUUAUCUGUGAUCUUAAAGACACGCAUCAUGACUGGCAAUAUCAAAGCCUGUUCUUUGGAUCCUGCUGUGUUUCAUGCCAGAUACAUUUUCAUUGUCCUCUUUCAAAGGCACUUGCAAAGUCUCUCUGCCAGAUCCUGGAAGUGGUCAUCUUCCACUCCUGGCAGUUGGCUUCUUGGCUGACUCUUUGUCCAGAUGGAGCACUGAUGUGGCCUCUGAAUGAAAAUUAGACCUCUUUUUCUCAUUAUGCCUUUGCUAACUUGCCUUGGAUUUGGAAGAAAUGAGGACAUACCAUUUUCUUUAAAACAACAACCACGCUGGCUAUAUUCAGAUAUAAUUCACAUACCAUACACCUCAUCUAUAUAAAGUGUACAAUUCAAUGGCUUUAGUAUAUUUACAGAGUUGUGCAGCCAUCACCAUAAUUUUAGAAUAUCUUUACGACCCUACCAGUAAACUCCCACUAGUGGUGUAUGAAGGUUCCAGUUUCUCCACAGCCUCACUAAGACUUUUUAAUUAUGUGUCUUUUUGAUAUAGGCAUCCCAAUGCUACAUGUGUGGUGGUGUCUCAUUGUGGUUUUGAUUUGCAUUUCCUUAAAGACUAAAGAUGUUGAACACCUUUUCCUGUGCUUAUUUGCCAUUCAUUUAUCUUCUUUAGAGAAAUGUCUAUUGAGAUCCAUUGCUUUUUUUUUUUUUUUUUUUUUUUUUGGAGACAGAGUCUCACUUCUGUUGCCCAGGCUGGAGUGCAGUGGCACGAUCUUGGUUCACUGUAGGCUCUGCCUCCCAGGUUCAAGCUAUUCUCCUGCCUCAGCCUCCCAAGUAGCUGAGAUUACAGGCACCCACCACCAAGCCUGGCUAAUUUUUGUAUUUUUAAUAGAGAUGGGGUUUCACCAUGUUGGCCAGGCUGGUCUUGAACUCCUGACCUCAAGUGAUCCACCUCCCUUGGCCUCCCAAAGUGCUGGGAUUACAUGCAUGAGCCAUUGCACCUGGCCAAGAAUGUUUGCUCAUUUUAAAAUAGGUUUUCUUUUUAUUAUUGAGUUGUAAGAAUUCAGUGUAUAUUUCAGGUACAAGUCCCUUAUCAGAUACAUGAUUUACAGAUAUUUUCUCCCAUUCUGUGUGUAUCUUUUCAAUUUCUUGAUAAUGGUUUUAAUUUUGAUGAAAACUUUUUUAUACUUGUACUUUUCGUGUCAUAUCUAAGAAGGUUUUGCUAAUCAAGGCCUAUAUUUUCUAAGAGUUUUAUAGUUUUGUCUCUUACAUUUAGGUUCAUGAUCUAUUUUGAGUUAAUUUUUGUUUAUAGUACGAGGAAGGGAUCUCUUGCAUUCGUGCUAAGUGGUAUGUAAUUUUGGUAGAGGCUAUACAGUGUGUAUACAUGGCUAGCCAUCCAAAAAAAAAGAAAGACUUCGGAUACUGAGUCCCUAAUGAGCUGCCCUGGCCAGAAGCAUUGCACCUAUGUGGCUGUUUCAUCAUUCAAAAUUGCUAAUUAAAGGUCUGCUAUCCACUUAACCAACAAUGUUUAUAUAUUUUUUUUUCUAAAAUGUAUGUAAAUAUUAUUUUUGCUUUUUUCAUGAUGUCCUUUUAUUUUUAACUGUCUCAAAAACUAGUUUGGAGCACCUUCAGUAAAAAAAUACACGUAGCAUGGUAUGUCUGAAAGAGCUUGAACUUAGAGUGCAGAAGACCCGUGGUAAGUGCUGUACCUGCCAUUUACUAGUUAUGUCCCUUGGGCAAGUGCUUCCUCUGAGCCUCAAUUUCCAGCAAAAUUGUUGAGAAGAAUCCAUGAAAUCAUGUUUAUAAAAUGCCUGGUAUGCCAUUUCUUGGCAUAUCUUAGUUACUCAGUAAAUGGUUACUGUUUUUGUAGUUGAUACUAAAACUGUAGCUAUCACUCAUUUUUCUCCUGUGUGGUCCCUUUUAUGAUUCCCCUAUUUGAAUAUGCCUUGGGUCAGUCCUUUUCUCAGAAAGUUAAUGUCAUUUUAUUUUCUAGCUAGGGUGAUUUACUCAAGCUAUUUGAGAGUUGCAGUCUCCUAAGUUUUCAGAGUGUGUUCCCAAGGGAACCAUGAAGAAUAAUAGUUUAUCUUGAUUCCAGGAAAGACAGUUGCUGAGGGAUUCAUGGAAUACACGUUUGCAUUUCUUUCCAGAGCAGCUCACAAAUUAUGUUUGUUAUAAAUGCUGGUUGCUUCUUUGCCAGAGAAGAAACUUCCUUGGAGUAUUCCAGAUUUCUAGUGAAGACAAAGAUUUCUUUGUCAAGAUGAGAAAGACUUUACGAGAUUGUGGGGAGGUAGCAUUGAGUUUAAACCAGUAGCAAGAGAUUGGUGAGAAAACAAGAUGUGACAUUCUGAAAAGGAAGGACAAACUGCACCAAUAGAGAGUCACAGAUACCAUGUUGCUGUGGAGGGGUUGAGGGAGUUAAUAACACUGAUAGUAAUAUUGGCAAUGAUAAUUGGUCUUGAGCAUUUAUCAUGUGAUAUGUGUAAAUGCUAUGUGCUUUAAUCAUGCAUUUAGUAUUAAAUAGGCACAGAGAUUCCAGUGAGUUGAGCUGAGAGUUAAAGAGAUUGGGUAACUUAUCCUGUGGUCAUAGAACUAGUAAGUGGCAGGCCUAGGAUAUGAAUCCAGUGUGGCUAGAGUUUUUUUUUUUUUUUUUUUUUUUUGAGACAGAGUCUUGCUCUGUUGCCCAGGCUGGUGUGCAGUGGCGUGAUCUCAGCUCACUGCAACCUCUGCCUCCCGAGUUCCAGUGAUUCUCCUGCCUCAGCCUCCUGAGUAGCUGGGAUUACAGGCGCCCGCCACCAUGCCUGGCUAAUUUUUGUAUUUUUGGUUGAGACAGAGUUUCACCGUGUUGGCCACGCUGGUCUCGAACUCCUGAUCUCAGGUGAUCCACCCGUCUUGGCUUCCCAAAGUUCUGGGAUUACAGGUGUGACCAUGCCUGGCCCAGUGUGGCCAAAGUUUUCAACAGAAAUAGUUUUCUCUUUUUCUUGAAUGUGUGGAAGACCUGAGAGCCCAUGAACCCUGUGGAGUGCUUUACCAUUUCUUCAGCUUUACUUAUUGAACCAGCUGUUCAAAAAACCAGACACUUUUCAGAGUAAAGAGGCCUCUAUUCGUAUUUACCCCAGGGCAGACAGUAUAUACCAGAGUGCCUGAGGUGAACCAGAAAGUGUGGUUGCCUGUAUAUAAGAGUUUUAAAACAAUACUAUUUGGAGCACUCCCCACAAAAAAGGACAUAGCCUUAUUUAGAACAGAUGGUAUAGAGUAAACAAAUGACAUGGACAAAACAGAACUGCUCAACUUCUAUUUUGAUUUUAUCAUCUUUAUCAGGAAAAAUGAUCUUUAAGUUGGAAAGGGUAGAAUAAACAUGGUUAGGAGACAUUAAAACCCAAGAUAGAAGAGAUAAUGAGAAUGACUAAAAAAAUGCCUUUACGCCUCCUGGGCACGGAAGGAACUUGCAGAUGUGAUUGUGGAACCACUUUAGAUAAUAUUUUGUGAAUCAAGGAGAAUAGGAUGCCAGAAGAUUGUAAAUGAUUUUGACAAACAUGUCCCAGCUUUCAAGGGGGAAAGCAUGGUUUGGAAACUACAGAUGGGUGAGCUUAAGUCAGUUUCUGAGGAAUUCUAGAAGCAAUAUUAAGCAGACGUUUGUGAACAUAUAAUAAGGCAGCAGUGAGUAAUGGGAGACAGAAAGGAUCCUCUAAGAACAAGUCUUUUUCUUGUUUAGAUGGGAUCAUUCGUCUGAUACAUGAAGGGAAUGCCGGAUAGAGAGUGAAUAUUGAUUUCAGCCAGCCACUUUGAGAGUCUCUGGUGUCACAGACAAGAUGGAGAGAUGUGACUAGCGUGAUAAUACAGUUUGAUGAGUUUAUAUUUGCUGCCAUAACCAGUGUGUGUGUGUGUGUGUGUGUGUGUGUGUGUGUGUGUGUGUGAGAGAGAGACAGCGAUUUUUUUUUUUGUUCUAAGUGACAGGGUCUUACUCUGUUGCCCAGGCUGGAGUGCAUGAUCAUAGCUCAUUGUAACCUUGAUCUCCUGGCCUCAAGCAGUCCUUCCUUCUCCGACUCUGAAAGCUCUGGGAUUACAGGUGUGAGCCACUGUGCUGGGCCCACAACUAUUUUAAAACUGGGUGAUGAACAGAUUGAUCAACUAAUGAAAUAGCUUCUGGGGCAAAAUGGCCUGUUGCUUGUUUUUAUAAAUAAAGUUGUAUUGGAACACAGUUGUGCCCAUUUGUUUAUUAUGUAUUGUUUAAGGCUGCUUUCGUGCUACAGUAGCAGAGCUGAGCAGUUGCUUUAGAGACCAUUUGGCCCGCAAAGCCUAUAAUAUUUGCUUUCUGGCUCUUUAACAGACAAAGUUUGCUGAUCUCUGGCCUAGACAGAACACUGGUUCUCAGCCUGCUGUACAUUAGAAUCACCUAAAGCAUUCUUACUAAUGCCCAAGCAUCUUUCCUCCUCAGCCCCUCCAACUAAAUCAGAAUCAGAGGUUGAGCCUGGCAUUUUUCUUUCUUUUCUUUUCUUUUCUUUUUUUUUUUUUUUUAAGAUUUCUAGGUGAUUGUAAUGUGAAGUCAGAGCUGGAGACCACUGGCCAGGAGGGAGGGUGCUAGUGGGGAGUGCAGCAAGGGCGUGUGUGCCAUCUCCUGUUUCCUAUGAGGGUUAAUGAUGUACUGUGCAAUCCAAUCUCUGGAUGACACAGAGGGAGAGGUGGACAUGGUUCUUUAGAUGACAGGGUAAGAACUGCAAAAAUUCUGGCCCUAAGGUAACAAGAUGAUGUUGGUAUAGUAAAAAAUAUAAAGGCCUUCCCUAUGUACUAAAAGUCUCUUUCAGAAGUGUCAGGUGGUGAUUUGGCCACACCCAGUGAAAUGGAUGUGAAAAUGAGUUAAGGGUUAACUGCAGACUCAAUAUGAGCCAACGAACAGUAUGUGAUAACCAGGAAACCCAAAACGAGAUAAAACCCAACAAUAACAACCAAGGCAAUCUCAGCCUACAUUGACAUAAUUACAGUGAAAGCAGGGAUAAAAUUUCUACUGUAUCUGCUCAGGUCAAAUCACACCUGUUGGAGAAACACUCUUUGUGGGUGGGAAUGUGGCUGGUUCAGCUUUGGAGUCACCUGGGGUAGUGCUUCCCAAGAGGCUGACCUCCACUGCCCUUAGAGCAGGGUGAGGUGCCACAGGGAGCAGUGCAGUCUUGUCUCUAAGAGGUGUACAAGUGGAUCAGAUGGCCAUUUGGUAGGGGUUAGAAAUGAAAGUUCAUCUUUGGGGAUUGUAUUAGGAUUUUCCAGGGAAAUAGAACCAAUAGGAUGGAUGGAAAACAAUACACGUAAAUCCUUAGGAUAAGGAAUUGGCUUAUGUGAUUAUGGAGGUCAACAAGUUCCAAGAUCUGCAGAAUGACUCAGCAUGCUGGAGAUGCAGGAGAGCCAGUGGUGUGAGUUCCAGUUCAAAGGCUGGCAGACUUAAGACCUAGGAAAACCCAGUGUUUCAUUUUGAGUCCAAAGGCAGGGAAAAACUGAUGUCGCAGGCUCAAGGCAGUCAAGCAGAAAGAGAUUCCCCCUUAUAUCUAGGAGGGGUCUGCCUUUUGAUUCUGUUCUGGCUUUCAGCCAAUUGUCUGGGGCCUACCCAUGUUAGGGAGGGCAACCUGCUUUACUCAGAUUGAAAUGUUACUUCUAUCCAGAAACAGCCAGAAUAAUGUUUGACUAAAUGUGUGGCACCCCAUGGCCCAAGCAAGAUGACACAGAAAAUCCAUCUAAUGCAACUUCCUCAUCCUGUGGAUGAGAAAACAGAGUCUCAGAGGAUGUAACUUUCCCAAGGUGCCCCCACUUGGUCAGUGGCCAAGGUAGCUCUUGGGUUAUUAGGUCUUCUCACUCCACAGCCCUAUGUUCUUCCUGCCACACUGUUCAGCAGGUGUAGAGGUUGUGUUAAUGACCUCUGUGGCCCUCUCCAGCCCUCAGGGUUAGACUGACUGUUAAAUGGAAGAAGUCAUUCCUCAGAAGGAGAGGCCUUAACCAGGAUGGAGAACUGCAGCCAUUGGGGGUGUGGUGCUUGAUUUUGAAGAGACCAUUGCCUAGAUACAGAGGAGGUCAAUGUAAACCCAAGUGAUGUCCGCUGUCUUAUGUACUUGGAUUGUGAGCUCUUCCUUUUGUACACAAACACUCUUCAGGCCCCUUCAGAGCCCCAAAUACUACUUAAUCCUUUAAUGCUGUUGCUGUCAAGAGGAUGAGGAAGAGGGAUGUCAGGCAGAUUUCAUGCUGGCGUGAAUAAUUAAGUGAGUGCAGGGCUACCAUCUGAAGCUCCAUGGGGGAGUUCCCUUUGUGCUGUCUGCAUAUGGCCUCCUCUUCUUGAAUCAGCAGAUGAUUCAGCCGGAAAGACGAAGACACUCAAAGGGACUCUUUUUCAGGGAUAUGUCUCAUCAUAAUAGGCUGUGCUCCCACCCCAUGUCAAAGAUGAUUCUAGGUGCUUCUUAUACAUUAUCUUUCCUGGUCUAAAAGACAACUAUGAAAGGCAAGCUACACAUUAUUAUCCCCAUUCCAUAAAUGAGAAGACUGAGCUCUGGAUGUAUUUUCUUCAUGUUGGAGGAAAAUGAUAUUAAUUGACAGGUCCCAGGUUUCUAAUGUAAUGCCCCCAUGUGUUUUCACACUCUUGGCACUGAGCUAAAACAUCUCAUUUUAGGAACCAAGAAUACAGUUAUUAGAAGACCACUCUCAGAGUCAACUCUCGGGUACUGUCAAACAGCAGAAUUUGAAAUUCCACAGUGGCUAACACGCUGACACCCAACACAGUUCAAGUGUUGUAUAAAUAAAGUCAACAGCCUGACUUUUGAGUAAAACAUAAUUUUUCAACUGCUGCCAAGAGGAAGAUAAUUGAUGAUAAAAGUGUCUAUGAACCAGAUAGAAAUGCAUUACGGAGGAAAGAACGAGAAAGAAGAAAUCAAGAAACUCAACAGGAUGAUGGCACGUUUAAUUCUAGUUACUCUCUCUUCAGUGAGCCCUACAAGACUAACAAGGGGGAUGAACUCUCCAACCGGAUCCAGAACACUUUAGGCAAUUAUGAUGAAAUGAAAGACUUUUUAACUGAUAGAUCCAAUCAGAGUCAUCUCGUUGGAGUUCCCAAACCUGGGGUUCCUCAGACUCCUGUGAACAAGAUCGAUGAACAUUUUGUUGCAGAUUCAAGAGCCCAGAACCAGCCCUCGUCUAUCUGUAGCACUACAACUUCCACACCAGCAGCUGUCCCCGUGCAGCAGAGUAAGAGAGGCACUAUGGGCUGGCAGAAGGCUGGGCACCCACCCUCUGACGGCCAACAGAGAGCAACACAACAGGGCUCUCUCAGGACCUUGCUUGGAGAUGGUGUUGGCAGACAGCAGCCUCGGGCCAAACAAGUGUGCAAUGUGGAGGUGGGCCUUCAGACCCAGGAGAGGCCACCUGCCAUGGCGGCCAAGCACAGCAGCAGCGGACACUGUGUUCAGAACUUUCCUCCAUCCCUAGCUUCAAAACCCAGCCUGGUCCAGCAGAAACCGACCGCGUAUGUGAGGCCAAUGGACGGCCAAGAUCAGGCCCCUGAUGAGUCUCCUAAGCUGAAGUCGUCUUCGGAAACCAGCGUGCACUGCACAUCAUACAGGGGAGUCCCUGCCAGCAAGCCGGAGCCUGCCAGAGCCAAGGCCAAGCUCUCCAAGUUCAGCAUCCCCAAGCAGGGGGAGGAGAGUAGAUCUGGAGAAACCAACAGCUGUGUUGAAGAAAUAAUCCGGGAGAUGACCUGGCUUCCACCACUUUCUGCUAUUCAAGCACCUGGCAAAGUGGAACCAACCAAAUUUCCAUUUCCAAAUAAGGACUCUCAGCUUGUAUCCUCUGGACACAAUAAUCCAAAGAAAGGUGAUGCAGAGCCAGAGAGUCCAGACAAUGGCACAUCGAAUACAUCAAUGCUGGAAGAUGACCUUAAGCUAAGCAGUGAUGAAGAGGAGAAUGAACAGCAGGCAGCUCAGAGAACGGCUCUCCGCGCUCUCUCUGACAGCGCCGUGGUCCAGCAGCCCAACUGCAGAACCUCGGUGCCUUCCAGCAAGGGCAGCAGCAGCAGCAGCAGCAGCGGCAGCAGCAGCUCCUCCAGCGACUCAGAGAGCAGCUCCGGAUCUGACUCGGAGACCGAGAGCAGCUCCAGCGAGAGUGAGGGCAGCAAGCCCCCCCACUUCUCCAGCCCCGAGGCUGAACCGGCAUCCUCUAACAAGUGGCAGCUGGAUAAAUGGCUAAACAAAGUUAAUCCCCACAAGCCUCCUAUUCUGAUCCAAAAUGAAAGCCACGGGUCAGAGAGCAAUCAGUACUACAACCCGGUGAAAGAGGACGUCCAGGACUGUGGGAAAGUCCCCGACGUUUGCCAGCCCAGCCUGAGAGAGAAGGAGAUCAAGAGCACUUGCAAGGAGGAGCAAAGGCCAAGGACAGCCAACAAGGCCCCUGGGAGUAAAGGCGUGAAGCAGAAGUCCCCGCCCGCGGCCGUGGCCGUGGCGGUGAGCGCAGCCGCCCCGCCACCCGCAGUGCCCUGUGCGCCCGCGGAGAACGCGCCCGCGCCUGCCCGGAGGUCCGCGGGCAAGAAGCCCACCAGGCGCACCGAGAGGACCUCAGCCGGGGACGGCGCCAACUGCCACCGGCCCGAGGAGCCCGCGGCCGCGGACGCGCUGGGGACGAGCGUGGUGGUCCCCCCGGAGCCCACCAAAACCAGGCCCUGUGGCAACAACAGAGCGAGCCACCGCAAGGAGCUGCGCUCCUCCGUGACCUGCGAGAAGCGCCGCACGCGGGGGCUAAGCAGGAUCGUCCCCAAAUCCAAGGAGUUCAUUGAGACAGAGUCGUCAUCUUCAUCCUCCUCCUCGGACUCCGACCUGGAGUCCGAGCAGGAGGAGUACCCUCUGUCCAAAGCACAGACCGUGGCUGCCUCUGCCUCCUCCGGGAAUGAUCAGAGGCUGAAGGAGGCCGCUGCCAACGGGGGCAGUGGUCCUAGGGCCCCUGUAGGCUCCAUCAACGCCAGGACCACCAGUGACAUCGCCAAGGAGCUGGAGGAGCAGUUCUACACACUGGUCCCCUUUGGCCGGAACGAACUUCUCUCCCCUCUAAAGGACAGUGAUGAGAUCAGGUCUCUCUGGGUCAAAAUCGACCUGACCCUCCUGUCCAGGAUCCCAGAACACCUGCCCCAGGAGCCAGGGGUAUUGAGCGCCCCUGCCACCAAGGACUCUGAGAGCGCACCGCCCAGCCACACCUCGGACACACCUGCAGAAAAGGCUUUGCCAAAAUCCAAGAGGAAACGCAAGUGUGACAACGAAGACGACUACAGGGAGAUCAAGAAGUCCCAGGGAGAGAAAGACAGCUCUUCAAGACUGGCCACCUCCACCAGUAAUACUUUGUCUGCAAACCACUGCAACAUGAACAUCAACAGUGUGGCAAUACCAAUAAAUAAAAAUGAAAAAAUGCUUCGGUCGCCCAUCUCACCCCUCUCUGAUGCAUCUAAACACAAAUACACCAGCGAGGACUUAACUUCUUCCAGCCGACCUAAUGGCAACAGUUUGUUUACUUCAGCCUCUUCCAGCAAAAAGCCUAAGGCCGACAGCCAGCUGCAGCCUCACGGCGGAGACCUCACGAAAGCAGCUCACAACAAUUCUGAAAACAUUCCCCUCCACAAGUCACGGCCGCAGACGAAGCCGUGGUCUCCAGGCUCCAACGGCCACAGGGACUGCAAGAGGCAGAAACUUGUCUUCGAUGAUAUGCCUCGCAGUGCCGAUUAUUUUAUGCAAGAAGCUAAACGAAUGAAGCAUAAAGCAGAUGCAAUGGUGGAAAAGUUUGGAAAGGCUUUGAACUAUGCUGAAGCAGCAUUGUCGUUUAUCGAGUGUGGAAAUGCAAUGGAACAAGGCCCCAUGGAAUCCAAAUCUCCUUAUACGAUGUAUUCAGAAACAGUAGAGCUCAUCAGGUAUGCUAUGAGACUAAAAACCCACUCAGGCCCCAAUGCCACACCAGAAGACAAACAACUGGCUGCAUUAUGUUACCGAUGCCUGGCCCUCCUGUACUGGCGGAUGUUUCGACUCAAAAGGGACCACGCUGUAAAGUAUUCAAAAGCACUAAUCGACUAUUUCAAGAACUCAUCUAAAGCCGCCCAAGCCCCAUCUCCGUGGGGGGCCAGUGGAAAGAGCACUGGAACCCCAUCCCCCAUGUCUCCCAACCCCUCUCCCGCCAGCUCCGUGGGGUCUCAGGGCAGCCUCUCCAACGCCAGCGCCCUGUCCCCGUCGACCAUCGUCAGCAUCCCACAGCGCAUCCACCAGAUGGCGGCCAACCACGUCAGCAUCACCAACAGCAUCCUGCACAGCUACGACUACUGGGAGAUGGCCGACAACCUGGCCAAGGAAAACCGAGAAUUCUUCAACGACCUGGAUCUGCUCAUGGGGCCGGUCACCCUGCACAGCAGCAUGGAGCACCUGGUCCAGUACUCCCAACAGGGCCUGCACUGGCUGCGGAACAGCGCCCACCUGUCAUAGGGACCUCACCCUGGGGCCAGAGUGGGCUCUGGUCUCCACAGAUGGCUCAACGUUUUUGGACACUGUGCUACUGAAACUCCCAGCCACAGCAUUUAUCAGACUGCGGUGAACAUUUCCUCAGCAUUGAACAAUGAUCUUUUGCAGGGCAUGUGUGUUUGUAUGUGUGGGUAUAUAAGAAGCCGCCUGUGUAUGUGUGUAAGAUACACAGCUCUUCAGAACACACCUUCUUUGUCUAGUUUCCAUAAUCCCAGGCUAGACAAAGUGAUCAGAGGUUUCUGACUAGAGGAAGUACACACACACACACACACACACACACACACCGUACACUCACACACAAUCACAGACACACACUUUCUAUUCCAUUCCAGUGCUAAACCGUGACUUCUUAGAAAAUUCAACCAAAAUCUCAUGGGUUAGUUAACCAGGUGCAAUACAGCACACCAAAAGCUUGACUGCCAGUGAAGAUGGACCUGCUCUUAUACUGUUGAUUACUUUCAGUAUUAAUAUACUAUUCCCCAAUUAUUUUUUGAUUGGUAUGUAUUAAUGGGUAAUUGAAUAAUGAAAAUAAGCCAGGUAUUUUUGUGCCGGAAGUUUACUAGAUUGCAUGUUACCAAAUACCCUGCUCUUCCUCUAAUUCCCUUCCCCCAUCUGACUCUAUUAUCAACUAAAUGCAUUCCAGGCAAACAGAUGGACACUCACAGCCCUUCCCAGCCCCACCUCCAAGUAGUAUGCAAAUGGCACUGAGAUUUAGCAAAAACGCGGCGUCUUUGAAAGUUAACAGACACUAAGGUAGCAGUGCCUGUGUGUUGGAGCUCAGUUAGGAGUUGAAGUUUUCUGCACCUGUGAUAACAAGCCCACCAGCCACAUGCAUUUCUUCUUCCUGCCACUGUGACUCGGUGGCUGUAGAGCCACAUGGCAUUUGUCAGCCAAUCUGUUUCAAGUCUUUUCUUUCCACCAAUAGCUUUCUUACAGAUUUUCUUGGCUAAAUGAGGCCAUUACCUAGAUUGUCCCUUCAGUAGGAGCCUGAAUCCUUCGCUUACCAGGCUGAGAGCUAUUUGCCAUGAUAAUGCUGAUUCUCUCACUCCUCAUGCAGAAUGUGCACCUGCAGCCCUUUGAUGCGUUUUGAUUUGGGGGCGAUUUUUCAGGCUUUGAUUAGCAGGCUGCUUGCAAUGCAGAAGAUCACAGUUCCUUUCUGGGGCAGCAGCAACCAGAGCCUCUUCCUGUGUCCUGUGUGUCUGGUAUGUUUACACCUUGCUCUGAGUUUUUCUCUUGUUUUCUUUUUUUAAUUAAGUUUACAUUUUAGUUUCUUUGACAUCUUGUUUACAGUUUUUGUCUGAUGUUUUUUCUUUUGUAGUGUCUUAUGCCCUAGAUUUAGUCAUCUUGUUAAAUAUAUUUGGAUAUGAAAUCUUGACGAAAAGAAAAUAACUCCUGAAAAAGAGGGUCUAUCUUGCCACACGUUAAAAACAAAAAUAAUGUCCUUGUGGCCUCUUACUUGAUAAAGUUGCACCAGGACGGUCUGAGAAAGGCAGGCGGUGUAAUAUGUGGUGCAAUCCAUUUUUUCAAGGUGAUGACGGCACAAAAUACUUAGACUAGAUGCUGAUCCAUAAACAUUCACUGAUAUUCUUACAGGUUGGUUUGCAGUGUUAACAUUUUUGUUAGCCUGAUCUGUAGGUGGGAAGUAAGAUCAUCAUAAUUCCUUAGCUCUGAGCACUGAUUCAAAAUUGUAUAAAUGACUGAACAACUUAGAUGAUUUGAAAUUAAUUGAAAAUAAGAAGGGCUUGUGGAAUUUGCAUUUGGCUUUGGCCUUCAAGCAUUUGGAAAUAUUAAGAGAAUUUCCAUUUUACAUGUCUCCAACUGGGGUGCUUCUUACAACCCUUUCACUUUUUUUUUGAGACGAGUUUCGCUCUGUUGCCCAGGCUGGAGUGCAGUGGCACGAUCUCGGCUCACUGCAUCCUCUGCCUCCUGGGUUCAAGUGAUUGUCCCGCCUCAGCCUCCCAAGUAGCUGGGAUUACAGGUGUGCACUACCAUGCCCAGCUAAUUUUUGUGUUUUUAGUAGAGACUGGGUUUCACCAUGUUGGCCAGGCUCGUCUCAAACUCCUGACCUCAGGUGAUCUACCCGCCUCCACCUCCCAAAGUGUUGUGAUUACAGGCGUGAGCCACCACACCCAGCCCUUUCACUAAUUUUUGGCAGAGUUCACAAUCCCAUCCUAUGUCAGAAACUUGAACCUAACUUAAGAAAUUUUGAGUCAUUUUUUUGGAGGACUGAGGCUUUGUUCUACCUACUCUUGAAGAAUCCUGAUGAAAUAUUCAAACACAUAAAGGGAUGGCCCUGGAGGUCUAUCCUGCAUACCUGGAGAGCUUCUCUGGUCCUGCCCACCUUGAAAGUUGCAGACUUUGUUGUAACAUCUAUGUGAUGAGCUUCCCUGUGAAGCCCCAUUUGACAGGUGGGCCAGCAGUGUUUUAUCAGCACUCUGAUGGCCCACAUUUCCCAGGAAAACUUCUUGAAACUUACCGUUGUGGGCAGUGGUCAGAGCGUGUAGUUCUUAUGACUGUCUUGUUUCAUCUGUGGAGCACGUGUGGAGCACGUUGGUACAGCAGUUUCUGUGGGGUUUGGCAUGGGUGAUUUUGGUUAGUAACCAUCCUCCAAUUGUUGCUUGUGAAAGUCAUUCAUAACUUGUUCCUUUUACUUAGUUUUGUUGUUACUGCUGUUGUUGUUGGUUUGGUUGGUUUUGAGACCGGGUCUGGCUCUGUAGCCCAAGCUGGAAUGCGGUGGCGCGAUCAUGGCUCCCUGCAGCCUCAAACUCCUGGGCUCAAGCAAUCCUCCUGCCUCAGCCUCCCAAGCAGCUGGGAAGAUAGGCACGUGCCACCACACCCGGCUAAUUUUUUCUUUAUUUUUUUUGUAGAGAUGGGGGUCUCACUAUGUUGCCCAGGCUGGUCUCAAACUCCUGGGCUCAAGCGAUCCUUUGGCCUCGGCCUCCCAAAGUGCAUGAGCCACCAUGCCUGGCCUGUUUAGUUUUGUUUCAAGUUGAAAUACCUUUCUUGUGUUUUCUAAUUAGAAAAGUAAUAUCUACUCAUUGUAAAAACUCAAACAGUGCAGAAAUGUAGAAAGUAGAAAGUGUAAGUCCCUGGUUGUCCCUUCUGCCUGAGACAACCACUGCUCACAGUUUGAUGUAUAUCCUUCCAGAGACUCUCAAAUUUAAGCAAAUAAUUUUUAUUACCAUGUCUUUUUAUUUGAAGACGUACAUUUGCCUCCAAAGUUCAACACAAGUUCAACUGACCAUAUCCUUCCAUGACCUGAAUAGAUGCUAUCCUUUAUCACGAUGUUCAAUUGCCUUUGAAAGAGAGUAGUCCAGGUAUAUUCCUGAUCAAAAUUUGGCAUUUUUGAUGAUACUACUCUACACAGAUCAGACUCAUGUGCAGAAUCGUGCCUGGAGAGAGAGGUUUGGUUAAGACAGAGAUUUCUGGAAACAUUCAAAUUGCAAAUGGAAACUUGAAACCCACAAUCUAAUGAGGAAUGUACUGGAAAAAUAAUCUGAAGAGUUGACAAAUUGUGUACUAGAUUGAACACAUGGAAUGCAAUGCAAUGAGACUUUCUGCACUAAAACUUAUCCUCAUAUGUACAACAAUGAUGUGUGUAUUAUAUAACAGUGAUGUGUACAUUUCUGACACCCCAUACAUAAUAUACACAGUUUGUAUAAAUGCAUACAUUUAAAAAUAUAUAUGUACAAUACAGCUAACAUAAAACUGUAGUACGCCUGAAGGAUAUUACUAGUGCCUAAUAUUGAGUAUGAGUCACUGCGUGUUCGCAUCAACUUGGAAGUGCAGUAAUUGUUAUAAAAUUAAUCAGUGCAGCCAACAUUAUUUAUGAAUCACAUCUUUGAAACUGUGCAGUAGCAUAUACAUAUAUAUUUUUAAAUAACAUUUUUCACAGUUUUCCAGAGUUACUGUUGAAAUCUGCAUCACCAAAAAAAAAAAAAAGCAAGAUUUUUUUAACAAUGUAGACACUCUUCAGACCCAGUAAUCUGCGUGUGAUUUCCUAUUUGUAGAUUCCCAAGAGACUUUAGCAGUCACCAGCCUUAAUGCAUGUACAGGAUAUUAUUGUGACUUAAUUUAUCUGCAGUUUUUAAUCCAUGUGAAAUUGGAAUUUAUAAACGGACUUGGAUUAAACAUGUCUGCCUUUCUAAGGUUGCAAAUGUUACAUUAAAUGAUUUAUGUUGUAAAUGAGAGAAGUUGAGUUGUACGUAAAAGACAUCCACCAAUUUCUGUGAAUAUUUUUACACGGAAACUUGAGAAUCAAAAUACGUUCAAGUCAGUUGUUCUGGCUCCCAGUUUAUAAUCUCGAAAAGCAAUCUUUUUGUUUCAUAAAUGGCUUAAAUGUAGCUCCCACAGAUUAUCAGUAUGAAGUCUGACAUUUUUCAUGGAAAAGAAGUAUGUUUUUCUUCAUUAUAACUAUAGUUUACUAUUUGUCUUUGCUAUUUCCUGAUACAUACACAUACGCACACACGCGCGCACAUGCAUGCACGUAUGCACAUGCACGCUCCCAGUGUCCCAGUGAAGGCUCAACAGGAAGCUUGAGAAGGUCAUCUCAAUGGCCACAGGGUUCCUGUUCAACCAGUAGCCCUGGGAUGCCGCUUUGCUUGUCAUUCUUUAGUGUCACAAGUUAGUUCCCUGACUUGUGUGCAGUCAGGGAACUGCACACAACUGAAACCAACAUGGUGGAAUCAUGUUUGCAAUAUUUGGUUGAGUAAAAUAAGAUAAUUUUGAACUAAAGAAGACGGAGGCAUUAGACCAGUGGCUUGACAUGAAGCAUCCCCUAUGUGGGAGGGUAAGUUUGUUAACUUCAUUUUUAGUCUUAUCUCCAACCCUUUUCCUUAUCCUCCUCCCCAAACUAAAGAAGCAGAAACAGCAACAAAAGCAAAACCAUCCCUUCACCUGAUCCAGCCCAUGUCCUUAGAUUCAAAUAUCCUUUGUCUUUUUCCCAUUAUACCAUCUGACAUAACUCACUCGUGUCUAGAGAGAAAAAUGCAGAAAGGGUUUGUUUGCAGAUGGGCAGUUCAGUUGAGUCCUCAUUAACCAGGCAGAGGGGUGCAGAAGAAGCCUGACUCAGGGUCACCAUGGAGAACUCCUCAUCCCAGAGAUGGGUGGGACAGGAACUUGGCUUUGCUUCACCAACCACUGAGCUUGAUACUCUUUCAGAGGUGGUUUGUGCUAAGAAACACCCAGCAGUCUUUCAAGAACGUUCUCUUCUGUAGCUUUGCCUGCUACACAGCUGAAGUCUGUCCCUAUAAGAAUUAUAUUUGUAAAAAGUAAUACAUUUUCGAAGAAACCCGGAUCAAGUGGAAUCUUGAAAGUUUUUUUAAUGAAAGGGGAAAAACAACCUGACCACAUAAACUGCACUUCCAACCAUUUGGAACCAGAGUUUAUGUCCUCAUUUUCCCAUUCUCAGAAGAGCACAGUUUUUCAAUAUUACAACUUCCUGGCAAAUAGCACAAGAAAUGUUCAGACUUGAGAUUUGUGUUCCCUUUGUCCAGAUUAUUCUGUAUAUGUCACCAAAGGGGUUAACUUGUUUGCUUGGCAUGAGGAAAAUUAUAAACUCCGUUCUCAAACUAAUUACAUCUGCCCACGGUUUUGGUUUUUAUUAUUUUAAUUGGCACUCCGAGGCAGCAGGGGGUAAAUUUUGUGUUGGCUGCAAGGGGAUUUAGGUUCACAGCUCUUACUCACAGUAAUGGGAAUCAAGGGAUUAAAUCUCUGUGUGUUACUUUGAAAAUCCACCUCUUACAGCCAAUUUUAUAGACAUUGAUCUGAGGGUUGAAUUCAGGGCACUAAUUGCCAGUCAGUACAAGGGUCAGCAUUUGUGUUGAAGCACCAGGGGUAUUGAUGUAGCCUGAAAAGCUGAAUCAGGGACUUGGGUUUUGUUUUGUUUUGUUUUUUUUACCCAUUUUUAAAAUAGGAAAGCUCAUCCAGAAAUACUUGGAUCUAGACAUGAUAUAACAUAGCACCAAUGUUUAGGAUUUUUAGAGUGCUGUUGGGUAAUUAAAAUAAUAUCAAUGUUCUA